AGUCUCGACGCUUCGGGGCCACCCCAGGGUCUGGUCCCUGACGACGCGCAGUGAGGGCCCCGCCGCUACCCCAGCAGUCGCCUCCCAAGUUCGCGGAACGCAGCUGACCGGCUCCCUCUGGACUGGGUGACAUGACUGCUCCCAAGCAGUCGUUUGUAAACUGAGUUUCUGUAAAACAAUUUUAUUUUUCAUAUGUGACUGUAGCGGGGUAUGAUUUGAACUUUGUUUUCCGUCCCCCAGCCCGGAUUCUCUGUCUUCUCCUGUACAGCCGUUCCGUUUUCUUACCUCGUCUCCGUCACCGAGGCCCUCAGCCCUGAACACAAGGACUGGGCAGUUUCCCUAUUGAUUCCUGAACCUGGAACUUAAGACAUCUUCCGAGGGGCCCCCCCUUGCCACACCCUCUAGCUGAUCGACUCACAAAUACCUGUGAUUUCUCUCCCCGUCUCCACCUCCAGGCCUGUUCCUGAACCCCCAGUUACUGGAACCCCCAGGAUGAUGAGAAGCGAGGGAUGCAAACCAGGAACCCCCAGUCUCAUGGGGAGAACGGAGCCUCACCCUGGAGCUGGGGAGAUCGUCUGGACCCAGGGGCUGAUGAUGAUGGGGAAAUCACCUACGAGAAUGUUCAAGUGCCCGCAGUCCUAGGGGUGCCCUCAAGCUUGGCUUCUUCUGUACUAGGGGACAAAGCAGCGGUCAAGUCGGAGCAGCCAACUGCGUCCUGGAGAGCCGUGACGUCACCAGCUGUCGGGCGGAUUCUCCCCUGCCGCACAACCUGCCUGCGAUACCUCCUGCUCGGCCUGCUCCUCACCUGCCUGCUGUUAGGAGUGACCGCCAUCUGCCUGGGAGUGCGCUAUCUGCAGGUGUCUCAGCAGCUCCAGCAGACGAACAGGGUUCUGGAAGUCACUAACAGCAGCCUGAGGCAGCAGCUCCGCCUCAAGAUAACGCAGCUGGGACAGAGUGCAGAGGAUCUGCAGGGGUCCAGGAGAGAGCUGGCGCAGAGUCAGGAAGCACUACAGGUGGAACAGAGGGCUCAUCAGGCGGCCGAAGGGCAGCUACAGGCCUGCCAGGCAGACAGACAGAAGACGAAGGAGACCUUGCAAAGUGAGGAGCAACAGAGGAGGGCCUUGGAGCAGAAGCUGAGCAACAUGGAGAACAGACUGAAGCCCUUCUUCACAUGCGGCUCAGCAGACACCUGCUGUCCGUCGGGAUGGAUAAUGCAUCAGAAAAGCUGCUUUUACAUCUCACUUACUUCAAAAAAUUGGCAGGAGAGCCAAAAACAAUGUGAAACUCUGUCUUCCAAGCUGGCCACAUUCAGUGAAAUUUAUCCACAAUCACACUCUUACUACUUCUUAAAUUCACUGUUGCCAAAUGGUGGUUCAGGGAAUUCAUAUUGGACUGGCCUCAGCUCUAACAAGGAUUGGAAGUUGACUGAUGAUACACAACGCACUAGACACUCAUGCCAACAAGAACCUGUGCCCCUCCUUCCUAACCUGAGGCCUGGGGUUCCUCAGACCAUCUCCUUCAUUCUGGGCAGUGCCCAGCCACCGGCUGACCCACACCUGACACUUCCAGCCAGUCUGCUGCCUGCUCCCUCUUCCUGAAACUGGACUGUUCCUGGGAAAAGGGUGAAGCCACCUCUAGAAGGGACUUUGGCCUCCCCCCAAGAACUUCCCAUGGUAGAAUGGGGUGGGGGAGGAGGGCGCACGGGCUGAGCGGAUAGGGGCGGCCCGGAGCCAGCCAGGCAGUUUUAUUGAAAUCUUUUUAAAUAA